AUUCCCAAUUUUAGGUGGCAGUCGCAACCCAUACUAUUCGGACAGAUGGCACAGAAACCGCUGCGCCUGUGAGUGACCGUGAAUGGAAGCCUCUCUCCCUGUGUCUCUUUCGUCUUGGCUUGUGGAGAUGUUGAAGGAAAGUUUGAUAUUUUAUUCAAUAGAGUUCAAGCAAUUCAGAAGAAAAGUGGAAACUUUGAUCUGCUGUUGUGUGUAGGAAAUUUCUUUGGCUCCACCCAAGAUGCUGAAUGGGAGGAGUAUAAGACUGGCAUCAAGAAAGCUCCUAUUCAGACAUAUGUGCUUGGUGCUAAUAACCAGGAAACAGUAAAAUAUUUCCAGGAUGCUGAUGGAUGUGAAUUAGCUGAAAACAUUACUUAUCUGGGUCGUAAAGGUAUCUUCACUGGAAGCUCGGGGCUGCAGAUUGUGUACCUCAGUGGGACAGAAUCCUUAAAUGAGCCAGUACCAGGUUAUAGUUUUAGUCCCAAGGAUGUGUCUUCUCUGAGAAUGAUGCUGUGUACAACCUCCCAGUUUAAGGGUGUUGAUAUCUUGCUCACAUCCCCAUGGCCCAAGUGUGUGGGGAACUUUGGGAAUUCUUCUGGAGAAGUGGAUACCAAAAAAUGUGGUUCUGCUUUGGUUUCCAGUCUUGCCACGGGCUUGAAACCAAGAUACCAUUUUGCUGCUUUGGAAAAGACCUAUUAUGAGAGGCUUCCAUAUCGAAACCAUAUCAUUCUACAGGAAAAUGCACAGCAUGCCACCCGGUUUAUAGCUCUGGCAAAUGUUGGAAAUCCAGAAAAGAAAAAGUAUCUUUACGCGUUCAGUAUUGUUCCCAUGAAGCUAAUGGAUGCAGCAGAACUGGUAAAACAGCCUCCGGAUGUCACUGAAAACCCUUACAGAAAAUCUGGGCAGGAAGCAUCCAUAGGAAAGCAAAUUCUUGCCCCUGUGGAAGAAUCAGCCUGUCAGUUUUUCUUUGAUUUAAAUGAAAAGCAGGGAAGGAAGCGUUCAUCCACAGGUAGAGAUAGCAAAUCUUCUCCUCAUCCAAAGCAGCCUCGCAAACCUCCUCAGCCUCCAGGACCCUGCUGGUUUUGCCUUGCUAGCCCUGAAGUGGAAAAACAUUUGGUGGUCAACAUCGGCACACAUUGCUACCUUGCCCUGGCCAAAGGAGGCUUAUCUGAUGACCAUGUCCUCAUCCUGCCUAUUGGACACUACCAGUCAGUGGUGGAGCUUUCAGCAGAGGUGGUAGAAGAGGUGGAGAAGUAUAAGGCCACUCUGAGACGGUUCUUUAAGAGUCGAGGGAAAUGGUGUGUUGUAUUUGAGAGAAAUUAUAAGAGCCAUCACCUCCAGCUACAGGUCAUUCCUGUCCCAAUCAGCUGCUCUACUACUGAUGACAUUAAAGAUGCCUUCAUUACCCAGGCACAGGAGCAGCAGAUAGAGCUGUUGGAAAUCCCAGAGCACUCUGACAUCAAGCAGAUUGCACAGCCAGGAGCAGCAUAUUUUUAUGUUGAACUUGACACAGGAGAAAAGCUUUUCCACAGAAUUAAAAAGAAUUUUCCUUUGCAGUUUGGAAGGGAGGUCCUGGCCAGUGAAGCCAUCCUUAAUGUUCCUGAUAAGUCUGACUGGAGGCAGUGUCAGAUCAGCAAGGAAGACGAGGAGACCCUGGCUCGCCGCUUCCGGAAAGACUUUGAGCCCUAUGACUUUACUCUGGAUGACUAAAACAAAGGGAAGAACUUUUUAUGAACUCCACAGGAAGUAGUAAAGCUUUUUUUUUUUUUUAAUUAAAAGAAUUUUUUUUGAGACAAAGUCUCGCUCUGUCACCCAAGCAGGAUUGCAGUGGCAUAACUGUGGCUCACUGUAGCCUCAACCUCCUGGGCUCUAGAGUUCCUCCCACCUCAGCCUCAUGAGUAGCUGGGACCACAGGCGCAUGCUACCAUGCCUGGCAAACUUUUUUGAUUUUUUAUAGAGACAGGAGGGUCUCCCUGUGUUGCCCAGGCUGGUCUGUAAUGCCUAGGCUCAAGGGAUCCUCUGCCUUGGCUUCUUAACCUGCUGGGAUUACAAGCAUGAGACACCAUUCCUGGCCUAGAAGCCUAUUUUUAAAGAAACUACAAUCUCCCAUGGGGACUGUUUCCCUGCCUCUUUUGUGCAGUCCCAUGGAACUUGCCUACAGCAAGAGGCCUAAGAUUGAAUCUUUUUGGGGAAAAGUCAUUCUAGGAUGAAAAUCCUAUGUUAAGGCCGGGCGCAGUGGCUCACGCCUGUAAUCCCAGUACUUUGGGAAGCCGAGGCAGGUGGAUCACCUGAGGUGAGGAGUUUGAGACCAGCCUGGCCAACAUGGUGAAACCCCGUCUUUACUAAAGCUACAAAAAUUAGCUGGGCGUGGUGCCAGGCACUUGUAAUCCCAGCUACUCAGGAGGCUGAGGCAGGAGAAUUGCUUGAGCCUGGGAGGUGGAGGUUGCAGUGAGCCAAGAUCGCUCCAUUGCACUCCAGCCUGGGUGACAGUGAAACUCCAUCUCAAAAAUAAAAGAAUAAAAGUAUGUCUGUCAUCCAGCUCCUAUGUCUGUUAUCCAGCUCCAAGUACAGCUUGUGUAUAUCAACAUUUUCAAAAACCUUUAAACUACCAAAUGAAAUCCAGAUGUUUUUCCAUGGUU